GGAGCCGAGCGGCGUGCAGAGGCUACAAGUGCCGUAGCUGGUGAUUGGGGGACUUUCUCCGGGAACCGUGCCGGGAGAGCGCGCGGUGCUGGAGCCGCACCGGGUGGCCGAAGCAGAAGACUUUCCGGAAGCUGCUGGGGGAUGUCUGACUAGCUCUCAUGGAGCUCCACUACCUUGCUAAGAAGAGCAACCAGGCAGACCUCUGUGAUGCCAGGGACUGGAGUUCAAGAGGGCUGCCUGGUGACCAGGCAGAUACAGCAGCCACAAGAGCUGCUCUCUGCUGUCAGAAACAGUGUGCAUCCACCCCAAGAGCAACCGAGAUGGAAGGGUCUAAACUUAGUUCUUCUCCAGCAUCCCCCUCCUCCUCUCUGCAAAACAGUACUCUUCAGCCAGAUGCCUUUCCACCAGGACUUCUCCACUCAGGGAACAACCAAAUAACAGCGGAACGGAAAGUCUGUAACUGCUGCAGCCAGGAAUUAGAAACUUCUUUUACCUAUGUGGACAAAAACAUCAACUUGGAGCAGCGGAACCGGAGCUCGCCAUCAGCAAAAGGGCAUAAUCACCCUGGGGAGCUUGGCUGGGAAAAUCCAAAUGAGUGGUCCCAAGAGGCUGCCAUAUCUUUGAUAUCUGAAGAGGAGGAUGAUACAAGUUCAGAAGCCACGUCUUCAGGGAAGUCUAUAGACUAUGGUUUCAUCAGCGCCAUCUUGUUCUUGGUCACUGGGAUCCUGCUCGUGAUCAUCUCUUACAUCGUCCCACGGGAAGUGACUGUGGACCCCAACACUGUGGCAGCCCGGGAGAUGGAGCGCCUGGAGAAGGAGAGUGCGAGGCUGGGGGCUCACCUGGACCGCUGUGUGAUUGCGGGGCUCUGCCUCCUCACGCUGGGGGGCGUCAUCCUGUCCUGCUUGUUAAUGAUGUCCAUGUGGAAGGGGGAGCUCUAUCGUCGAAACAGAUUUGCCUCUUCCAAAGAGUCUGCAAAACUCUAUGGUUCUUUCAACUUCAGGAUGAAAACCAGCACGAAUGAAAACACUCUGGAACUGUCCUUGGUAGAGGAAGAUGCGCUUGCUGUACAGAGUUAAUUCUGGUUGUGAAUAUCUUGAGAGUCUGCCUUGGCAUUUUAUAAUAUGAAAAAAGUUAAUUUAUAAAAAUUCACAGUGCAAUUUAUUUGCCUGGCAAGAAAAGUUUAUUUCACAAACCAACAGCCAGUAAGUGUUUUUGUUCUCUAUGUGUCUUCUAUUUAGAAGAAAAGCCAUGUAAGAUGUAUAAGAAACCACAACCAGCCACACCUAUCCUUCUGAAGAGCUGAAGGCUAAUUAAUCUGUAAUGGCCAAGAACUUCUACUUCGAUAGAAAAAUAUUUCUAAUGACCCAGUCUACAAAUUAUUUCUUUUACACAAAUAUAUGAUGUUAUUCUUUGGACACUAGGUGGUCCUACACACAGUAGGAUCAAUUGCUAAUCUACUUUGUGAAAAAGAACUAAGCACUAAUCAAUAAUAAGGCUUACAUCUAAUUCUCAAAGGUGCUUAUCCAUUUUCUUGCUAAAUUAUCCUUCUUGUAAUUUGGCUAAACACUAAAACAUGGAAUUUUUAGUUUGAAUAUUUUGAAGUUUGAGGAUGUUGGGCUUUCCUUAUUGUAAAAAAUGUUAUGUUUGAAAUUAUUCCUGUUUUCAAAAAUGGUAAUUAAGUCAUUAGGAUAAACUUUCUAAUAAAAAAAAAUUAUGUAAAUCAUUGUAAGACCAAUGUGAAUUUAAACCACAGUGUUGGUGCCAGAUAUUAGCCAGGGUCACAGGCUCUUUUUUAAAAUGAAGUCAAAUUAGUUACUGAUAUAAGUUUUAUAUUUUGUGAUUUUGCCAUCAUACUGGUUAUCUGUGCUCUUGAAGUCUGCUGGUUCUCACACCAGCAGCAAGAGGCAAGGCAUGAGACAUUUUAAAUAUAUUUCCAGACAUCUAAACAUCUAGACAGGCCUGAGUCAUGAUUGGCUCUGGUGUGCUUCCAGGUAACAUCUUGUUAUUGCUGUUUGGGGAAAACCACCAAUAGAAUUGCAGCUAGACUUUUGGGGACUGUGCCUCGCAGGCUGUAUCACUUGCUGUAGGCCAAGCAACGAGCACUUCCCUCAUGGUAGCAACAGUCCUUAAGCCCAAAGCCAAAAAAAAAUAAAAUGGAAAGAGAGAUUCAAUACACUGAUUUAAUGGGGACUGUAGUCAUCGUCAGAACUCACCUCCCACUCACAGUGGUCUAGAUGUCAUUCAGCAACUGUGAACUCUUGCCUCAUGCAGCACAAACUCUUCUCUAAGAGCAGCAUGAUGAGCAAGGUGCUCACUUUGCAAGACACACACUGGGUGUUCACAGUGACAGACCGCCUCAUUAUGGUGACGGUUCAGAAAAGGGAUGGGAAAUGCAGCCUCAGAAAUACCUUACAUUUUGCAACUCUGCCUGGAGGUUUUUCCAACCUGUGCUCUAAGAGUUGUUGUAACUUCCAUGAUUGUGUUACCAGGAUCAGGGGGUCAUUCUUAAAAAGAGGACAGGAGCUGGGAAUUGGUAUGAGACAGCAGGAAUGAGGAAGUAAGAAAGUGAUUUCUUUGCAGAUUUUUAAAGGCUAUUUCAAAUGUCUGAAGUUUGUGGUGUUGUGGACAACUGUGGAAUACAUGGGUGACUUUGGCAAAAUGUGUGAAUCAGGAUAUUUAUGUGGAUGAGCUCUCAUGGGUGUCAGAUUGAUUUGAUGAGUGAGGUAUGCUGCAUAUGACUUAAGGGUUGAACUGAAAUACAAAAAGGGAGGCUCAGAAGAUAGUAAAAAGAGAGGAUGGGCAUAUGAAAGAAUUAUUAAGUAAAAAUGAGAAAUUAUAUGGCCAUCAGAGGAAGCUAGAUGUAGUUAAUUGCCUUAUGUUAUAGAGCAAUACUGAUUACUGAAAAGAAAGAAUUGAGAUGACAUAAACAUGAUUUUUGCUUUCUGUUGCUGUAUUUUUGUGCUUUUUGAACAAACUUUGUUUUACUGUGACUCUCAUUUCAUGAUUUUUGUUGAGGCUGCCUUACCAGUGGUAUAAGUUUUAUAUUCUGAAGGUUUCUAAGUCCAGCUCUAGCCUGCUUAAGGAUCCACUUUGGAUGAUGUUGAAACAAGAAGGAAACGAUCUGCUGAGUGAGUAGGUCUGAGCUGUGUGUUAAAAAAAGAAGGCAUUAAAAAAAAGAAGGCAUUAAAGAAAAAACUAAUGUUUAUUCAUAGAAGCUAAAUGAGAUCAACUGAGUUUUUAUUUAUUGGUGAAACAGGAUUAAUUAGCCAAAUGGCAGACUAAACUGAAUUAAUGUGGAAUCAAUUUUCAGUUUAUGAAGGAAGAGGAGUUUGGGAAUCAAGUGUUAGGAGGUCUUUUCACUUGAUAAUAAAGCUUUUCAUGUGGAAGCAUUUAAUGAAUCUUGCAGGGCUACCAAAUAAUAUAGAUUUGAUCUAGAGGUAACAUUUUGAAAAAUGCCAUUUUGGAAAAAAAAUAUUCAACGGGGGAGAAAAAGACCUAACACAUCAAAAUACAUUUCCUUUCUUUUCCCUAGAAUGCUAUAAUUUCCUUUAAAAUUUAAAAUCGAAAUGUGGUAAGUAAAUGCACACUUCAACAUUAUUUAAAUCUGCUAACAUAUAGAGCACCUCUCUUUUAAGGUUCUACUUAUCUGAGGGCAAACCAUUACACAUUACAUGAUUUUGAAAAUCAUCUGAAUGACUUCUUUUGGGCUGUGGUGACAUUAUUCAGAUACUUGCCUUAAUCGACUUUUCCCUGGGUAUUUGGUUUAUGUAGCCCUUAUCCAUCCUGCCUGAAUUCAAUAUGAAGAUUACUUGAAUUUAAAAUGAUGGUAACACAGGCAAAGAAAAGCCAUGUGCUUUAUUUCCUGUUUUUCCCAAUCUGACAAAGAGUGUUUUUGGCUCUAGAGGUACUUUGGCAAGACCAGGUGAUGCAUUCUAUAGACAUUGGGCAUACAAUACCUAUAGUUUUGGUCUUGCAUCCUUCAUGGAGAUUUGUGACCUUCCGUCUGUCUCUUCAAUAUGGUGCUGGUUGUUACCUGUGAAAGUUUUUAUUGCUAGUCCUAGAGAAGAAAAACAUAUUUCAGUGGUUCUAGGUCUUUAGCUUAUUUACAUGGUUUUAGAAAUCUAAACUCAAGAGUCAUCUUCCUAGUCUCAAUGAGAAGACAGCUCGUCUUUCAGCAGUGUGGCCCAAUGGGGUGAGUUACAGAAAGAAAGCUGUCUUUCUCCUUUAUUACUGGGAUCUACACGCUGCUGGUGGAUGAUUUAAGGCUCCUAAUAUCUUUAUAAGCCAGUUCUUUUUAGGGCACCUUAAACUGUUAGUGGUAGAGUUUGCAAAGAGUUUUCUUUGCAGCGCUGUGUGUCCUUCCCACCCAUUGGGAGCUCUUAAAGCAGAUCACAUAAUAAGAUGUACUGGCCCCUCAUAUAAAGAACAGCUUUUCGUCAUGCUCCCCACUGUGUAGGUGAUUUAUAGUUUACAGGAAGACAAGACUGCUUGGAACCAUGAAGUUCUUGGAGGCCAUGGUUGCUUUUACCCACAUGACUGCUAUAACCCUUGAUUCUGUUCUAUCAAGUUACUUGCCUUGAUAUCAUCACAUGCUUUGCUGUCUGCUUAAAAUAUGAGUUCAUCCCCCUCAUACUUAUUUGUUUUAGGGACCCAAUUGGACCAGUGCUGGCACAUGCCCUUCAAGGUACAAUUUCUGAAAAGAGACUGCGCUGCCAAACUUAUGUGUGCCUUUACCUCAGUCCCCCCAGUAUAAGGGGUGACUUAAUCUUGAUAAAUGAGUGACUGAGCACCAUGCUAGUUAAAUAUUGAGAAUUAAAAGCCUGAACCCAAUGGCUCUAUUUUUUUUUACCACCUUCUGACAAGCAAAAAUUCUAGGCAGGAGCAUGUGAACAUUUUGGUCUUCAUCUUUCACGUGUGCAAUGAUAGGUGUAUGCAAAAUUUUACUUGGAUUAAUUGUCAAGUUAAAAAAGUGUUCUAUAUGUAUAUCUCUUAGGAGAAGGUUUUUCAACCUGAAGGUCAGAUUUCAUUGCAGCAAUUAAUGCCAUCAAAAAAACGUGGUCUGACAAAAAAGAUUCACAACCUUUGCCAGUGGUUCACCUAUUACAGCAAGAUGUAAUACUAUCAAUACUUACUGUUCUCUGUAAUGGGUUUAACCUUUCCCAGAAUUGGACAUAAAGAAUGACUACGAUGAGAAGAUUAUAAUGAAGUCUUACUGGCUUUUCCUAGUCUAAAAAGAGUACUUAAGAAAGAGAAUUAACAUAUCAUUUCCUUUUGGCUGAUUUUUAGCUAUAUCUGUUUUUGGUUCAUAAUAUUCUAUAUUAUCAUCUCACAAAUUUUAUAAGUCUUGGGAAAUAAUUUGCCUGCCUAGUGAAUUGACACUGUAAAAAGCAAGACGUUAUUUUAAACACAUAAAACUAAUUUCAAGAAUCUGUGGCUUACACUCAAGAGUGUACUCGUGGUUUAUGUUUGUGUGCAGAUUUAUGUGCACUCAAGUCUAUGUGCAUUUGGACUAUAUUUUAUAGUUAUACAGCUUUAAUAUCCAAAGUUAUUGUUAGAAUAAUUUUAUUAUAGGAAUUUGGCAUGCCUUACUAUUGACAUUAAGAAGAAGAGAAGUCUUUCACAAGUCAUGAAUGAAGAAUUUGGAAUCAGCCUCAGAAUGAGAUGCCAUAAUUAUUAUAAACCUGUUUUGGUUGUUCAGCCUCCCACAAAUAUUUAUUAAUUUGUUUUUUAACCUCUCAAUUUCAGGCUCAUGAGAGUGUGAGAUAUUUGGAAAUUAUUUUACCGUGAAUUGUUAUUUUAUUUCAGGGGACUAUGGGGAGUAUAUUCCUUUGUUUCAAAUUUGGGUAACUCUCCUGUGUUUCAGGAACAGCUCUCCCUAUUUUUUCACUGCCAUCUUCAGGCUUCCUAGCCAGGCUCCAAACAAAUGUCAUAUAAGAAAGAAAGAUUAAUUAUUACAUAUUGUGUAUUGAGAGUUUGUACCCUGUGGUUCUCAUCGUGCUGUUAAUUUUACUUUUCUUGCCAAACAAAAAUAAUUUGACAUUGAUUAUGUGCUUUUUGAUAUUUUCAAGGGCAAUUAUUAAGGUUAUGAGCUCUUUCUUAGGGCACUUGAUGCCUUAUAUGUUAAUAGCAAGUGUGUCAUAUCAUUUUAAAAUAAAACUAUUCAAAGGCUUUAUUGUGUUUAUUAAGCUUAAUUUAAAUUGGAAUCUGUAAUGCUGAUUUGGUCUUUUAAAAUUAUAUUUGAAAUUAUUUGUCCAAAAAAAUUAAAAUGAAUAUUUACCCCUAA